GGGAGCCACAGUGGGGCCUGUGUGUUGGGCAUUUUCAUGUCAGCAUUUUUUUUUCCCAAAGCAGCCAGUUUCAUGGUUGGGUGGUUCCAAAUGUAAGAACGGCCCUUCUUCCCUGUGACUCCCACCAAGUAGCUCGGAGCAAGUCCACUUUGUAUGAAAUGGCAACGAUUUGGAAGAGUGACCUUCUCUAGGCUAAACAACUGUGCCGUUGACCAUUCCUCAUAGAUGGGUUUUCCUGAAUUUUCACUUCUCUGAGAGCUUUCGGGACAAGAGUCCAAUUUUAUGGUGACCCUCCCAAAUAGUGGCACCCAGAAAGGAACACAGUUCCACCAAUGACCAACCAGUGCUGAGUACCAUGGGGAGUGGACAUGCACCAAGAACGCUAGUAAAGCCCAAGAUUGGGUUAACAUUUUCGCAGGCUCAAUCACACUGUCGGCUUGGGUGAAACUGGUGACCAACUAAAUACUGAGCUGGUUUUCCAAGGGAUAGCUUCCAAGCCACGUCCCUUCAGUUCCAUGCUUGUGCAAUUGAAUUGAAUUCUGUGCAAUUGAUUUUUUGGAUGCUCAACACCACACUUCACAUUAAUCCCUGUCAUGUUGCUUUUGCCCAGUGUUCUGGCAUGCUGAGAUUUUACAGUCAGGGAAUUGUGGGGCUGAAAGGCUUAUUUGUACAGUUGACAGCUGUAGUCAUUUUCCAAUGACUUCCUGUCAGGGAACCUCCUCUUCCUAAGUCUACCCCAGUUCCUUCAGUUUCCUGCCAGUUGAUUUUCUUGAGCAUGAUCCAGCUCUGGGCCUAAUUCUUCCAGGAUUUAUCUCCCGAAGGUGAGAGACAACAGUGUUUUCUUCCUGCAGAUUCCUUUUCUCUCUGCAUCUCUCCUCUGUUCUGCCCCUGAUUUUUUAUUCCUUUGAGUCUUUGGGGGGUUGGUGGUUGUACCUGUUGCUUUGACCACUCACUUUAUCUUGUUCCCUGCAGCUCUUGACAGCCCAGCUCCUUAUACCCUCUUAUAUUUGUUUUUAGUGAUUUCCUGGCCUUUGACCCAUAGCUAUCUCUGGUCCUUAAGUUUCUCAUGCACCCUCUUUUAGAUUCCCAGUUCCUUGACCUUGCCCCCCAAAUUCUUGCUGCCUGAUAUCUGAUGACACCUUGCAGCUCUGUCCUUCACAGGUUUGGCAAGUUCACUCUCUGGGGCUUCAACCAAGGCAUUGCUAAAUAUCACUGUUGAGGAUUGAGACUAAGUUACUUAGUUAGAAAUCAGGACUAUUUUGAGUAUAUAUAUCAACUAGUUUAUGAAUCCACCUAAUGGCACUGCAUCUGGCCUUUUCCACAGGGGGAUUAUAGGAGACCUUAUCAAAUGCUUUGCAAGAAUGAAGGAAUACUACUAUAUCCAUAGAACCCUGGUCUACCAAUAUGGACUUCUCUCUUCAAAGGAAAAAUGAACUUGAUUGGCUCUGACUUGUUCUUGAACGUGGCCCAGAGUUUCAUCUUGGUACUUUUACACAUGGAAACAUUCUAGAGGCUGGUCUAAAGGACUGUCCACACCAAGGGAACAUAGGCUGUUAGGCUGGAAAAUAGUGUAUCAGGAUUUCAUCCAGGAAGGUCACAGCCUGUUGGUCUAGAAGAUCAUGUAAGAUGCUAUUCAGCAAGUGUCACAAGUUGGCCUGAUACAAUCUAGUCCAAAGUCUUCACCAUAUACUCAUACCAACCUGUGAUGACUCUCUUUACUUCUUUGGGAAAAGAAGGUACCUUCCAAAAGAUAAGAGCGAAGUGGAGCCAAGGGGAGUCCCUAAAUCGUCCUUCCUGACCGAGGAGAAGAGAGCCAGACUGAAGACCAACCCCGUGAAGGUGCACUUUGCUGAAGAAGUGCUCAUCAGUGGACACAGCCAGGGUAAUUCUCUGCUGUGUAUGCCCAACGUGCUCAAGCUAUACUUGGAGAAUGGACAGACCAAAGCUUUCAAGUUUGAGGCAAACACAACCGUGAAGGACAUCAUCCUCACCGUGAAGGAGAAGCUGUCCAUCCGAAGUAUCGAGUACUUUGCACUGGCCCUGGAAGAGCAGUACAGCAUCUCCCGGCUGCACCUGCUGCACGAAGAGGAACUCAUCCAGCAGGUGGUAGAAAGGGAGGAGUCACAUGACUACCGCUGCCUCUUCAGGGUCUGUUUUGUUCCCAAGGACCCCCUGGACCUCCUGAAAGAAGACCCCGUGGCCUUUGAAUACCUCUAUCUGCAGAGCUGCAGCGAUGUGCUCCAGGAGCGCUUUGCUGUAGAAAUGAAAUGUAGCUCUGCACUCCGACUCGCGGCUCUGCACAUCCAGGAACGGAUCUACGCCUGUGCCCAGCCACAGAAGAUCUCUUUAAAGUAUAUAGAGAAAGACUGGGGAAUAGAGAACUUUAUAUCUCCAACUUUACUCCGAAACAUGAAAGGCAAAGACAUCAAGAAAGCCAUUAGCUUCCACAUGAAGAGGAACCAGAAUUUGCUGGAACCCCGACAGAAGCAACUUAUUUCUGCUGCCCAGCUACGUUUAAAUUAUCUACAGAUCCUCGGAGAACUCAAGACAUAUGGUGGAAGAAUCUUUAAUGCUACUUUAAUGUUACAGGAUAGAGAAUCCUACAUUGCCCUUCUAGUUGGAGCCAAGUAUGGGAUUAGCCAGGUUAUCAAUAGCAAACUCAACAUCAUGUCCACAUUGGCAGAGUUUGCAAACAUCAGCCGUGUAGAGCUAACGGAAGAGUCUGAGAAAGUGAGCGUCGUCAAAGUGUAUCUUCAGGACGUCAAGGUUCUGACUUUGCUGCUGGAAUCCAACAGUGCAAAAGACCUAGCCUGCCUGAUUGCUGGGUACUACAGGCUGUUGGUUGACCCAGUUACCUCCAUUUUCCUCUGGCCUGGAAACAAACAACAAGCGCACCGGGUAUCUGCAGAAGAAGGCUAUGAAUCCAGGGCCUGCAGUGACUCAGAGGAGUCCUCUGAGGUGGACUGCGUACUCGAACCUCUCUCUGACAGGCGCCUGGUGAAACUGGCACCCUGCAGAUCACUCAUAAAGGAGGAGCAGCCUCCUGGGAACAGCCCCACACCUGAGGUGGCUAGGAGGGGCCCCAGCACCUGCGGGGCCAGCAGCACGACAGACAGUGCCGAGUCCGAGGCGUCCGACUCAGCCAACACUGAGAGCCGCGGCUACAGGACCAGUGGCUCGAGUGAGUCCAUGGACGCUCUGGAAGAGGAUGACUUAGACACCUGCUCCUCCAGCAGGUCCACCUUCUUCCACUUUGGCUCGCCAGGCCUCGCAGAGAGCAUUGACUCUGACAGCCAGGAGGAGAGAAGCGGGAUUGAAACCAGUGGCUUCCUCUGUCUCCUGGACCUGGCCCAGAGAGCCAACCCCCAGUGCCAGAAGACAGAGUUUUCCGAGAGUGCUGCUUUGGAGACAUUUGGCUGGGCACCAGAACUGAGCACAGUCAGGCUGGACCCCAGGCUGUAUGAAGGCAGCCACGCUGACUACUACAGCCUGUGUUCCAGUGUCUCCCCGGCCAGCUACCUGAGUGACAGUUCCGAGAGUACAGCUUCCCGGCAAGGGGGAGCCCCGCCAGCCUGGGGUCAGCAGGGCUGGACUGAGGCCCAGCCCAGUUCCAUGCUGGAACCCCUGGCCCUGCACCCACCACUGGCCUUUGAGGAUGGCAGCUCAGAUGAGGAAUACUAUGACGCGGCUGAUAAGCUCACUCCCCCAGGCCCCCCGUCAGGGCCCAGAGAUGUUUCUACUGCAGAACCCAGUGCCACAAGCUUGCAGAAUAAGGCCAGCACUUCUAGCCCUGAGAACAGCCUGCCUUGUGGGCCAGAUGGAAGACAGCCAAGCAGGAGGGGAGGGGUGAAGAAAUAUGCCAAGACCCUGAGGAAAAGAAGGUCUUUCCUACAGACCGACUACACCUCUCAGGUCUCAUUUCCCCUGGUGCCAUCAGCCUCCCUGGAGAGUGUAGACGACGUGUGCUACUAUGACAGGGAGCCCUACCUGGCCCUUGGUGCACCCUCCCCAACUGUGUCCUCUCUGCAGGACAUGCAGGGUGAGCCUGGCCUUCUGGAGACCAAGGCCUUGGGGCUGCUGGCUCCUCUGAGGGAGACCAAGAGCACAAACCCAGCCUCCAGGGUCAUGGAGAUGGAGCCCGAGACCAUGGAAACCAAAUCAGUCAUCGACUCUCGAGUGUCUUCUAUUUCUGCCAUUCGCUUCCGGAUUGACCCCAACAAUAAAGAGAAUUCUGGUGUUGUCCCUGCUGCCAGCUCCUCAGCAAGCACUCCUCACUGUUCUAACCCAGGUUCAUCUGGCCCAGAUACUGCUCAGGCAAGGCCUUCCCAAAUCUUACCUCUAUCUCAAGACCUGGAUGGGAUUGCCCCCAAAGAACCAACCAUAGAGCAUGGAGACAGCUCCUUCUCCCUCUCCAGUGGUGACCCUAACCCAGACAGAGCCUGCCUGGCCAGCAACCCAGGACUAAAUAAUGUCUCUCAAGGAGACACACUAGAGCUCCAGUUGGAGCCCCAUGUCCAGUUGGAAAUGGGAUUGGAAUCUUUUUGUACAAAUCAUAUACAAGAAACUGCCCCCAAAUACACAGAGCCUUUGUUGUCUCCUAGAGAUGAGCCUAGAAGUGAUGAAUGUGGAAUAAAUCCAGGAGAGAAGAUAGCUUCUAUCCCUACAAAGGAAGAGCCACAAGGACAACUAUCUCUGGAAAGAGACAGAGAAGUUACAAACAAAAAUGGCACCAACGUAUUUCAGGAGGAGUCUAGGAAGGAUUCAGGUGACUCCCCGGGUGAUGUGUCAAAUAAUGUUUCACAGACUCUUGAUAUUAGCUCUCCAGCUGGUAAAAUAGUAACCUCCCUUUCUUUAGAUGCUCCUGUAACAGGGACCGAGCAGAUCCCACCACAUCCCCCUAGAGACCCUCAAGGACAGAGCAGAGAACCCCCAGGGCAAGGCUGCCAGGCUCAAGAACAAAAACUAUUCGUAGAGUUGGAUUUAGACCCUGAUUUCUUUCUUGGGAAGCAGACAGUUUCACCAGCCGUCCCUCCAGAGGGGAUCAAGGCAGAGGCACCUAACCAUGUGACAGGGCAAGAUAUAGCCCCUAGGGACAGCCCUGAGUGGGUCUGUUUUAAUCCUGAGCCUUCCCUGCCAGAACCACUACCAUGUCCACAAGAGGAUCCUCACUUAGAAACUUCAAACCAUUGCUUACUCUCAGAAGGCAAAAGUGACAGCUCUAGCAUCUGCCUUUCUGCUGAGAAGUCUUUUCUGUGCUUUGCCCCAGAAAGCCAUCCUGAAGUCUCUGCCAGUCUCAGGGUGGCCACAUCUUUGGGUUUUGCAGGCAUGAAUGAGAUGGUGGCUCCCAGGAUAGGGAUGGACCAGUGCAGCUGUCAGUUCUCCUAUGCCACAUGCUUCCGUGGCCCGCAGCCUGAGACAGAGGAAGAAGACAGGGACUUGGAAGCACACCCCAUGGCCCCCCUCACCUCACCGCCCUCUGCGGGAAGCCCGGUGGUUCUGCCCUGGAGGCCUGCCCGAGCCCACAGCUGCACCACCGCACCCCUGUCGAGGAAAAGCCACAUCUGGCCAGAGUACUGCUCCAGGGCACUGAGACAGCUGAAAGCCACCCCUGCCAGCACCCCUGAGGGCUUCAUCCAACUCAUGGAGAGCUUGCUGGAGCUACAAGACAUUUUAGAAACUUCCUGGGGGGUUGGAAACAAACAUCCCCCAGAGAAGUGCACCUGGCACUUUACCGAAAGCCGGAGCCGCCUCUGCAUGGGCUCCCAGAAGCUCCUGUCGAGCUGUCGGCAUGUGAUCAGAAUGGACCAGUCCCCCGAAGAGAUGCAGGGGGCCGUGCGUGACACCUUCCAGCACCUGGUCCAGCUGGCCGGCCUGUGCUUUCAGUUCACAGACUGUAGCCGCUGCUCCGCCCGGCACAGGGAGGCAGCGGGGAACCUGAGGGAUGUGGUGUACACCUACCAUCAGUUUAUAGAGGCUGCUAAAUCGACCUGCGAGAGAGGCUACCACGACCUGAGUGUGAAACUCCUGGCCCGUCAGUGCACGGCCCUCACGGCCGCCGUGUUCUGUUUGACCCAGAAGUUCCGGGCAUCCACGGCCCUGUAAACAGGUCAACGGCCCAAGGGCCUCCUGCCCUGUCCUGCCUUGGACACUUCCCUGAGAAGCCCCUUCCACUCUCCCACCCACCCUCUUCAAAUGUUUACUAUAUAGAGUAUUCAAAUAAACUGCUGCUUAAUCUUG